ACUGUCUGCCGUCGCGUCGCAGUUACUAAGGCGUGGGGAAGAUAGCGGCAGGCACCGCAGUGGAGCGGCUCCGAGAUCCCCGGGGGGCUCGCAGGCGCGCAUCCCUCCUGACUGGGACGUCGCCUCCGCAGACCCCUCGGAGGCUGAAGCGACGCCGGAGGCAGGCAAAGAAACAAGUGAAGAAACAAAAAAAAAAGGAAGUUAAGGGGCCAUUCCCAAAGUCAAAGAUCAAGGAGAUGGCCUUCUCAGGAAUCUACAAGCUGGAUGAUGGGAAGCCUUACCUGAACAACUGCUUCCCAGCCAGAAAUCUGCUUCGCGUGCCGGAGGAAGGCCAAGGACACUGGUUAGUGGUUCAGAAAGGUAACCUCAAGAAGAAGCCCAAGGGUUUGGUUGGAGCACAAGCUGAACGUCGGGAAAGCCUGAAGGCGACUUCUUUUGAGUUCAAGGGGAAGAAAGAGUCUCGGCGGGAAAAUCAGGUGGACCUUCCUGGACAUAUCCUGGACCAGGCUUUUCUGCUGAAGCACCACUGUGUGAGGAAGCCAUCAGAUCUGUGCACCAUUAAUGUGAGUGGCCUGAAGUUCUCCAAGGCCAAGGAAAAUGACUUCAAGCAUUUUCAUUCUGUGAUUUAUAUCAAUGCCUCAGAAAACCUGCUGCCUCUAGAGGCAUUUCACACGUUUCCAGCCCUAAAGGAACUGGAUCUCGCAUUUAAUGGCAUCAAAACUAUCUACGUGAAAUAUGGAGACUUUAAGUUAUUAGAAUUCUUGGACCUUUCCUUCAACAGCCUGACUGUGGAGGCCAUCUGUGAUUUGGGGAUUCUGCCACACCUCCGUGUCCUGCUCCUCACAGGCAAUGGCCUUACCUCCCUGCCGCCCAAUUUGGCCGUCGCAGAACAGGAGGCAUCUGUAACAUCGCUGACAAGCAAGAGGUACAUCCUGAGGUUCCCAGCGCUGGAGACACUGAUGCUGGAUGACAACAGACUCUCCAACCCCAGUUGCUUUGCCAGCCUGGCUGGGCUCAGGAGACUGAAGAAGUUAAGCUUGGAUGAAAACAGGAUUAUCAGGAUCCCAUACCUACAGCAAGUUCAGCUCUAUGACGAGUCAGUAGACUGGAAUGGAGGCAGGGGAAGUCCCCAUAAAGAGCCCCAAUUCAUGCUGCAGUCCAAGCCAAGGAUGCUUGAGGACUCAGAUGAGCAACUGGAUUAUACUGUACUGCCCAUGAAAAAGGAUGUUGACCGGACAGAGGUUGUGUUUUCAUCUUACCCUGGAUUUUCAACCUCAGAGACAACCAAGAUAUGUUCACUUCCUCCCAUAUUCGAGAUCCUUCCUGUGAAGUCACUGAAGGCCAGGAACCAGACGCUGGCCCCACCCUUCCCAGAGCUGAGAUACCUUAGCCUGGCCUACAACAAGAUCGCAAAAGAGGAUGCUGUCCUACCAGUAGCUCUCUUCCCAUCUCUCUGCGAGUUCGUCUUUCAUAACAACCCUCUGGUGGCCCAUACACGAGGGGUCCCUCCACUGCUGAAGAGCUUCCUCCAGGAGCGACUGGGAAUCCACUUAAUUCGAAGGAAGAUAGUAAAGCCUAAGCAUCAUGUUUUGAUGUCUCGGAAGGAAUCAUGGAAGGUGAAAAGCGAAAUCCCAAAGGUGCCGAAGCAGCCUCUGGUGCUCCAUCACCCGCGCAUGACGACAACCAAGUCUCCCUCAAAGGAUAUGCUAGAGCCAGAGGCAGAGCUGGCUGAAGAUCUGCCCACUACCAAAAGCACUUCUGUGGAGUCAGAGAUGCCCACUGAGAACCUGGAAGGCCAUUCCCCGUCUUGCCGGACCUUCGUGCCACUGCCUCCCAUCUGCUCCAACUCCACUGUGCAUAGUGAAGAGACCCUGUCCCACCUGAGUGACACAACUGUCCGCCUCAGCCCAGAGCGCCCAUCAGAUGAGGACUCCAAGAGCACAGAGUCCAUCUUCCUGACCCAGGUGAGUGAACUGCCUUCCUCCGUCAUCCAUAAGGAUGAUUUAGAGUUAAAGGAGAAAGACCAAAAGAAACCACCAACGGCACCCAGAGAGGUGAAAGGGACUCGGAGGAAACUCCCAACUGCCUUCCUUCCCAGCAAGUACCACGGCUAUGAAGAACUGCUGACAGCCAAGCCUGAUCCAGCCUUCAUUGAGCCAAAGGGAAUCCAGAAGAAUGCACAAGCCCUGCAACAAAUGCUGAAGCACCCACUCCUGUGCCACUCCUCCAAGCCCAAGCUGGACACUCUUCAGAAACCCUAUGUUCACAAAGAGAAACGGGCCCAGAGAAUCCCGAUUCCACCCCCAAAGAAGACUAGAGCCCAACUUCUGGAUGACAUCUUCAUUCGCUUGCGGGAUCCCCGGAACAUUACAGAGGCUCCACUAGGUGCUGUCCUGCACCAGUGGACAGAACGGCGGCUGGUGAACCACAAGCAGUACCUGGAGGCCAAGAGGCUGUUGAAGGAGUUCCAGGCACGUUACCGGCAGCUGGUGAGUGGCUCUCUGCGCACAGUGUUCGGGACUACCCCGCUCCCCAUGGCCUGCCCAGCGCUGAGUGAGAGCCAGCCCAAGUUCGGCCACUUCCUCGAGUUCAUGGAUGAGUUCUGCCAGGAGCCCACAGCCAGUGACUCACAAGGCUAGAGCUGUGCAUGGGGGCUGUGUGCACCACCCGGCCUGUGCCCCAGCUCUCCCCGAGGGCUCUGUGCCCUGGACCGCACCUCAAGGUUGACCAGCCGGCCACAGGCCUCAGAGCUCAGCUGGGCCCCACUUGCUGGCCACAAGGUGGCAUCCCCUUGUCAGGAUCUCCCCUCCUUGGCCCAGGCAUGACCUGGUGCCUGGCCCAGCGGCAAUAAAGAGUGGGUGCACAGGGCAAUAGACUGGGUGCCACAUGCAUUCUUUCUUGGAACCCAGGCCACAGCAGCAUUGUCACACUUCCCUCUAAAAAUGGUUUUCCAGUUCAGAUGCAACAGGGAUACAUUUGUUCUCUGUUGUAUGAGAAACUGACACCAAGGGGAUCUUAACAAAUUCCUGAACAAUGGCUCCAAAAAAGGGUAUUUUUAAAAACCAGAUCUUGUGAGUACAGCCCUAAUGUGCAGGGACAGUGUCAUCCUGUAUAUUCGUUCUUUACUCAGACUCUUUCUUGGUUCCUUCAUUAGGAGCAUGAAUGGUUGAAUGUGAACAUGACAGUAAAUUGGAGCAAACUGUAAACUGGACAUAACUUAUGCCAAAAGACGUAGUUGUACACCAUGGAAACCCCAUCCCUGCUCCUAAUCUCUACUGCCAUUCUGAAUGCCAAAGCAAGACAUCCAACAUGGGGCAUCUCCCAGAGCACAUACAGCACCAAAAAUCCACACACAGCCUAAGCUUAACCCAUGUUUUUGUCUGAGAUUGUUCACCAGAGACAAGACUCUGACUAUAAACAGAACAUCCACUUUCAUGAGUUUCCUUUACUGUAUUCUCAACUUGGGCCUUGCUUCAAGCAGGCAAACAUACAUUGAAGAAUGCACUUUGGUACUGUUUAAAUAACAACACAUCAGCCCACUUGAUUCCAUGCCAUGUCCUUGCUGACAGAAACAUCCCCAACAGGGCAUGCCCUGGUCCAAGUCCUCUGUCUUUGUCAAAAUGCUCUUCUGAUGAGUUGGAGAGGAGGCAGCCAGCAGUGGCAGUCCACAAGGAUCCAGGUACCUUCUCCAAUCCUAAAGCAGACAGCAGGUUGAAUAAAACCAAUACACAACCUAUUUUCUAGGCAGGAGGGGAAAAGGCCCUUAGGACAAUAAUAUUUGUACAAAGAGUUGAGAGUAAACAAACAGUGUAUCAGGUUCAAAAAAAAAAAAACUAUUCGUUGGCAUUUAAAUUUUUUUCCCUUGCAUAGUAUCUAUUCUCUCACUAGGACUUUUAAGUGCUCUGCUGGAGGCUCAGCGUUGGUAAUACCAUGUUUGAUGCAAACUUGAACCCAAUGCUCUCAUUGGUGGCACAGCUUUGGAGGGUGGUGGCCCCAAGAAGGGGCAAUCUGCCUGCUGCUAUAUUAAUCUGGAACCAGGGCCAACAGCUACUCUUGAACUAUGGUAUUUGAAGAGCGAGUUCAUUGCCUGUUUUACCUUAAAUGACAGGAAAGGAAGAUGAACAAACCUUGCUUUGCCUUGGCUUCAAACUAGUUCUUGAUUUAAGACACCAGAAAGGGAGAGAGGGAGUCUGCUUAGAGUUUGAGGUUGCCUCUCACAAGAUGACAGUUAAAAGUUGCCACCUUACUUAAAAGGCAUUAAGGAGGCAUUUACUCACAAAGGAGAGAGAGUAAAUUUUUUUCUUAAGAGGAAAAAAAUACUGAUAAUACAUAGAACAAUCUGCACAUCCAGUCUUGGCACUUUUUCCAAUUUGACUGAUCUCUAAACUGGUGACCCUUGCAUAUAUCUUAGUCUCUUUUCUACAAUCUUCUUCAGAAAGCUACAGCAGCUAACAAUCAUGUAUAAAGAUGCAUUUCCUAGAUCAUCUUCAGAAGAAAAUCUCUUCAGCACUUUCCCUAGAAUCUGUCUCCUGACCACCCCGCCCCAGACCUGCUUUCUCUUUUGAGAAUUCAUAACCAGGUAUGUUUAGAUACCAGUUCAAAAGACCACUCUAUGGGUUGAUGAGGAAAAGGCUGCCUGAGGACAAUUUAAGACCAUAAUGAGUUUCCAAUUUUUAAAGAAAAUUUGGCUAGCUGGCUUUUAAUUCUUAAUUAAAAUCAUUAAAUUUAAUUAAAAUUAUUCCAAUCAAAAUAUAUCACUUUCCAAGAUUCCACAUUCAUAUUACUUACUUAUACUAUGGAGACUUUCUCUACCUGAGCAUGUAUUCAGGGGCUAUAGGUACAUUUAACUCUAACUAACUGAAAAAAAUCAGGAAGAAAAAACUAUUAAAAUAAAAUAACCUCCUAAAUCAUUUGGGGGUAUCCCCAUCA